AGGUGCUCCGCAGCCGUCUGUGCCACCCAGAGCCGGCGGGCCGCUAGGUCCCCGGAGACCCUGCUAUGGUGCGUGCGGGCGCCGUGGGGGCUCAUCUCCCCGCGUCCGGCUUGGAUAUCUUCGGGGACCUGAAGAAGAUGAACAAGCGCCAGGGUGUGUUGCUGAGAGUGAGUGGUCCCAGUGGAGGGAAGAUCUUUGGAGAUGUGGAUGGGGGCCCAGGAAUUGAGACAGCACAGUGUUGAUGGACCACCCACCUGGCUCUGCAGAUCACCCCAACAACUGCAGGAUUGUGAAGAGGAAGAUUGAGGCAGGUACCAAACUCUAUUACCAGGUUUUAAACUUCGCCAUGAUCGUGUCUUCUGCACUCAUGAUAUGGAAAGGCUUGAUCGUGCUCACAGGCAGUGAGAGCCCCAUCGUGGUGGUGCUGAGUGGCAGUAUGGAGCCGGCCUUUCACAGAGGAGACCUCCUGUUCCUCACAAAUUUCCGGGAAGACCCAAUCAGAGCUGGUGAAAUAGUUGUUUUUAAAGUUGAAGGACGAGACAUUCCAAUAGUUCACAGAGUAAUCAAAGUUCAUGAAAAAGAUAAUGGAGACAUCAAAUUUCUGACUAAAGGAGAUAAUAAUGAAGUUGAUGAUAGAGGCUUGUACAAAGAAGGCCAGAACUGGCUGGAAAAGAAGGACGUGGUGGGAAGAGCAAGAGGGUUUUUACCAUAUGUUGGUAUGGUCACCAUAAUAAUGAAUGACUAUCCAAAAUUCAAGUAUGCUCUUUUGGCUGUAAUGGGUGCAUAUGUGUUACUAAAACGUGAAUCCUAAAAUGAGAAGCAGUUCCUGGGACCAGAUUGAAAUGAAUUCUGUUGAAAAAGAGAAAAACUAAUAUAUUUGAGAUGUUCCAUUUUCUGUAUAAAAGGGAACAGUGUGGAGAUGUUUUUGUCUUGUCCAAAUAAAAGAUUCACCAGUAAA